CUUGGUCUGAAGUUUGUCUUUCUUGGGCGGGACAUCCUUGCCCGGCUUGGGGGCUGUCUCCAUCUCGCCCACCCGAACGGCGAUCCACGUGCAAAACUCUUCUCAGCUGCCACACAGUCGGCUUGAAAACUCCCGGAAGCCCUCUGUCCUUCAUCCAAUCAGCAGCGUACCAGGCCAGAUCAGAAAAGGGAGCUCAGGUACCUUCCAGAGAGUGAGACCCAGCGCCCUUGUCUCGCACCCAGUAGGCUUUCAUCCCCGCCAUGGCGGAGCUGAUCCAGAAGAAGCUACAGGGAGAAGUGGAGAAAUAUCAACAGCUACAGAAGGACUUAAGUAAAUCCAUGUCGGGGAGGCAGAAACUUGAAGCACAACUAACAGAAAAUAAUAUCGUGAAAGAGGAACUGGCCCUGCUGGAUGGGUCCAACGUGGUCUUUAAACUUCUGGGUCCGGUGCUAGUCAAACAGGAGCUGGGGGAGGCUCGGGCCACAGUAGGGAAGAGGCUGGACUAUAUCACAGCUGAAAUUAAGCGAUACGAAUCCCAGCUUCGGGAUCUUGAGCGGCAGUCAGAGCAACAGAGGGAGACCCUUGCUCAGCUGCAGCAGGAGUUCCAGCGGGCCCAGGCAGCAAAGGCAGGGGCUCCUGGCAAGGCCUGACCCCAUGGUGGGGGGAGGGGAGGGGAGGGGAGGGAAUGAGGCAGCUCUAGGAUCUAUACUGUAGCUAAUAAAAUGUAAAAACACCUGGC